ACAGACGUCUCUGCAGGCAAGCUUUUCUGUGGUUUUGCCAUGGCUCGUACUAAACAGACAGCUCGGAAAUCCACCGGCGGUAAAGCGCCACGCAAGCAGCUGGCUACCAAGGCUGCUCGCAAGAGCGCGCCGGCUACCGGCGGCGUGAAAAAGCCUCACCGUUACCGCCCGGGCACUGUGGCUCUGCGCGAGAUCCGCCGCUACCAAAAGUCGACCGAGUUGCUGAUUCGGAAGCUGCCGUUCCAGCGCCUGGUGCGAGAAAUCGCCCAAGACUUCAAGACCGAUCUUCGCUUCCAGAGCUCUGCGGUGAUGGCGCUGCAGGAGGCUUGUGAGGCCUACUUGGUAGGGCUCUUUGAGGACACAAACCUUUGCGCCAUCCAUGCUAAGCGAGUGACUAUUAUGCCCAAAGACAUCCAGCUCGCUCGCCGCAUUCGCGGAGAAAGAGCGUAAAUGUAAAGUCACUUUUUCAUCAGUCUUAAAACCCAAAGGCUCUUUUCAGAGCCACCCACUU